GCGGCUGGCCCUGUGGGGUGGACCAGGGGUUUCUCCCCAGACGCCUGUUGGGGCCAGGGCUGCCCCCUCAGACCUCCAAGACGUCGAGUGUGGAGGACACCCUGGAGGAGGAGAUGGAACCCUCCUGUUUGCUGGGGCUCGGCCCCCGGUGAGGCUGGCUGCAGGUGACCACAGAGACCUAGCCUGGUGUCGUGCGGCCGCUGGGUCCGUGAAGGGGAGUGAGGCACUCCUCACCCUGUGGCAGCUCCUAGUCAGGAGGCCUCUCCCCUCCACCUGCACGUCAUGUGGCUGUGGCUCCCAGGACCAGCGCCUGGAGCGGGUGAGUGAACGUCCCUCUCCUCCGUGGGCACUGCCUCCGCUGUGAGCCACCCUUCAGGCUACGUGCAUUUCCGCCUGUUCUCAGGGUUUAACCGAAACCGAACAUUAACCGUAGCCCUAACGCGGCUGAGGGAUCCAGGCCUUGCCUCUGGGCCGGGUGAGAGACAGACACUCGCCAACCAGUCCGCAGUGGCUCCCCGUGUGUGCGAGGCUCCCGCCUGCGUGUGUGCGUGUGCAUGUGUGCCUGCGCACAGGGGAGGGAAAGUUCUUCAGCUGCCGAGGGCGGGAGUAGGGGCUGGAGCAGCACCCUGCGGCGAGGCCCCACAGGAGAAUCGAUGGUUCUGAUGCUGUCAGCCUCUGGGUGCAAAUUCUGAGGGCCCGGGAGCGUCUGGCGGCCCUGAGCAGCUUGCUGGGGAAGCUCCGUGGAGGAGGAAGUCCGGAGGUCGGUAAGCUCCAGGAGGGGUCUGCUGGGGGGCGAGAAUGCUCUGAGCAAGGUCCCAGAAGUCCAGAGCUCCUGAGGGACCCGGGACCAGGGGCACUGGGGAGUUUCAGGGUUGGUCGCCGCCACAGCCCUCACAAACGAGGCCACUCUCUAGGACUGGCCACCUUCUCACCUCGGCCACUUCACAGUCCUGGGGGGCAGCUGUGGCUCUUGCUGGGAACCACCUGGACCUCCCUGGGGCUUGGGGGUGGGGUGGUGGUGAAGUGAGGCCCACCCGUCCGUGGCUCACUCCUGCCACCUAGAGGCCACUGUUCCUCACAGGCUCUGGGGCCAGUCACCUGCCUCUGCCCGGGGGCGGGACCAUCCCACCGGAUUGCAGGUUCCCUGAUCACCAGGAUGGGCCUACACCUCUCCGCCUGCAGUAGUUGCUUCCACGCAGGACUAGAGCAUGUCAGGGUUCGGGGCUCCUGUCAUAGCGGAGUGGCUGCGGCCCGCAGGUCAGAGGCACCCGACCUCUUCUGCUAACCCCCUUCCCUGCCUGUCCCGUCCGCUCCUUUCUCUCCAUCACCUGCCCCUGCCAUGAACCAGGCCACCAGUGACCCCAUCCACACCUGUCCGACCAGGCUCCCCACGUGCCCUAAUGCAGCCCCGUAGGCUGGGCCCACGGCUGACACCCCUUCCUGAGGGAUCCCCGACCUGCCAGCCGUUGUCCUUAAGACGCCACAGCAUCUUGACCUCCCCGUCUGCAGCCUCUGUGGGCCUCCACUGGGACCCACUGAGACAUGUCAGGCUCCUCACGAGCUCUGUCUUGUGUGGCCAUGCCCAGGGCCCCAGGACGUAGAAGACCACCUGGCAUCUCAUGGAGGAGGAAACAGGGCCCAGAGUGGGACCUCCACUCAGGCUCAGCAAGGGCCGAGUCCCAGUUCCUGGAGUCCUAGUUGAGGCCCCUCCUACACAGAGCACAAGGUGGAAUUCACGGGGUCAUAAAGGCAGCCAGUUCUACCAACACACAGUUAUGCAAAUAUUUUCUUAAAGUGUGAUAUCAAAACCCAAGUGCUUCUUUACCAAUCUGCUGAACAAGAUGUGACUCACUGAACAGCCUCUGCAGUCCCAGCAGCAGCGAGUGUGGGGGUGCGAGGCAGUUCCCAUCUGUGCCGGGUCAGCCACGGGCCCAGCUGACCAGAUUUGGUUCAUGGCCUCGUUCAUAACUGAACGAACGACACCUUUCUGCUAGAGGUCGGUAUAAAGGAGAUGAUGGGCCGGGCACGGUGGCUCACACCUGUAAUCCCAGCACUUUGGGAGGCCGAGGCGGGUGGAUCACCUGAGGUCAGGAGUUUGAGACUAGCCUCACCAAUAUGAUGUAACCUCGUCUCUACUAAAAAUACAAACAUAUUAGCCGGGUGUGGUGGCGCAUGCCUGUAAUCCCAGCUACUUGGGAGGCUGAGACAAGAGAAUUGCUUGAACCUGGGAUGCGGAGGUUGCAGUGAGCCAAGAUCGUGCCACUGCACUCCAGCCUGGGCAACAAGAGUGAAACUCUGUCUCAAAAAAAAAAAAAAAAAAAAAAGGAGAUGAUGGUUUCUUCCCACCAGUUUAUUUUCUGUCAGGGGUUUGGUCUCUGGGUCUCUGACCCCCUGGAUUGUUGAGACGCCUCGCACUGUUCCCUCCCAUCUUGCCCGACCGCCCCCCACCAGCUCCCAGGCCCAGUAUGUCUCUGUCCCACCCCAUCGUCUCUAUAGGCCCUGUCCUGCAGUGGGUUCUGUCCCUCCCUGCAGCUUGGUAAGGUUGUUGAGGCUUCAAUACACACUCCAGACCACAUCCCUCUCCCUCCCAACUCUGGGACACUCUCUGCACCUCUGAAAAGAAACUCCCAGCCCUUCUUGUGCCUCUCCCUUCCUCUGGGCACCCCUUGUUCCUUAUCCAUCCUGGCUGGCCUGUGGCCUGUACUUCUGAUCUGCACACAGGUAUCACAGAGGACAGAGACCCCAGGGCCCCAGCCCCUGGUGGGGGCGGGGAGUGCAAGGGGGCAGUCGUCUUUGUUCUCGACCAGCUCCCAGCUCCCUAGGGAGAAAUCAGGUGGGGAGCGGCCUCACUGCUGGCUCCUUGAUAGUGACUUGCUCCAGAGGUCCGUGCUGAUACCCCAGACCCCGCCCCACCAACACUUCAACUGGGACUGCGGCGUAUGCACAACUGCACAGCCUCCUCUGGCAGCUCCUUGAUGCUUCUGGGACGUUGACCCUCUCUCCUUUGCACCUCCACUCUUAGGAACUUGCAGCUCUCUGGGGCAUGUGAUGUGAAUCAGCUGACAUCAUCUUGACGGGAGCCCUGUGAGGCGGACACUUAACUCCAGUUUCACAGGAGGGAGCCAUGGAUUUGCUGCGGGAGCUGAAGGCCAUGCCUAUCACGCUGCACCUGCUCCAGUCCACCCGAGUCGGGAUGUCUGUCAACGCCCUUCGGAAGCAGAGCUCGGAUGAGGAGGUCAUUGCACUGGCCAAGUCUCUCAUCAAGUCCUGGAAGAAGCUCCUGGAUGCUUCCGAUGCCAAAGCCAGGGAGCGGGGGAGGGGCAUGCCUCUGCCCACGUCCUCGAGGGAUGCCUCAGAGGCCCCGGAUCCCAGCCGCAAGAGGCCGGAGCUGCCCAGGGCACCGUCGACUCCGAGGAUCACCACAUUUCCUCCGGUGCCUGUCACCUGUGAUGCCGUGCGCAACAAGUGCCGCGAGAUGCUGACCGCUGCCCUGCAGACGGACCAUGACCACGUGGCCAUCGGUGCGGACUGCGAGCGCCUGUCGGCUCAGAUCGAGGAAUGCAUCUUCCGGGACGUUGGAAACACAGACAUGAAGUAUAAGAACCGUGUACGGAGUCGUAUCUCCAACCUGAAGGAUGCCAAGAACCCUGACCUGCGGCGGAAUGUGCUGUGUGGGGCCAUAACACCCCAGCAGAUCGCUGUGAUGACCUCAGAGGAGAUGGCCAGUGAUGAGCUGAAGGAGAUCCGUAAGGCCAUGACCAAGGAGGCCAUCCGAGAGCACCAGAUGGCCCGCACUGGCGGCACGCAGACAGACCUGUUCACCUGCGGCAAGUGCAGGAAAAAGAACUGCACCUACACACAGGUGCAGACCCGCAGCUCUGAUGAGCCCAUGACCACCUUUGUUGUCUGCAACGAGUGUGGAAACCGCUGGAAGGUGGGUGAGCAGGCUCAGGCUGCCCCUCCCAGCUCCAUUCUCUGGAGGUGGGGUGUCUCAGCCUCUGUGGGGUCUGUGGUGUGAACUGGGGAUGGCCCUGCCCAACCAGCCUCCUGGGAGUCUUGGGCAUGGUGGGUGGAGAGCCCAGCCUUGGGUGAGCCUGUGCGGCCUUCCACUCUGGGGGAUCUCAUGUGGCCACAAGGCUGGAGGCCUCACCCCCUUUCUCGCAGUUCUGCUGACCCCUCGUGUAGAUGUGCUGCAGCCUUGGGCCCUCCCCGGCCCACGUCCUCCGUUGACACAGCUUCUCUGGAGACCCUAGAAGGCGGCAUGUCCUGCCCUCAACCUGCCUGCCUGGAUUGCACCUUUCUGCCCUUUCCCCCUCAUUAUUAAAUGUUUCUUUUUGCCA